GCAAAAGGAGCCGAGCGGCUUCUGCUCAAUGGCGGAAAAGCCGCCGGUGCUCUGACGGCCUCGUUCCCCUAGCAGUUGCGGGGGAGUUUCCUGCCGGCGCGGCUGGAGUCUCUGAUUCUCAGGGUUCGGUGGUUGGAAGAUGCUCCAGAGAGACGAGGCUGCGGCGGAGGAGGUGGCGGCGGCCGAAUCGGCAACGGCGCUAGGGUGGAGAGAAGGCGGCAUCGGCGGCGGCGGCGGCGUGAGGGGCCGGGCGGUGUAAACAGCCCCGGAGGCGGCGGUCGAGACCCCGAGGGGGAAGCGGCGGCUGAGUCAGGGUCGCGCCUCCGUUGGAAACUUGGGCUGAGUACCGCGGCGGGCGCGAGCGAGGCGCCCUAGACAUCUUCUCCCUCCCUUGCCUCAGAUUUAUUGCUAAACAUGGGUGCAUUUUUGGAUAAACCCAAAACUGAAAAACAUAAUGCUCAUGGUGCUGGGAAUGGUUUACGUUAUGGCCUGAGCAGCAUGCAAGGAUGGAGAGUGGAAAUGGAAGAUGCACACACAGCUGUUGUAGGUAUUCCUCACGGCUUGGAAGACUGGUCAUUUUUUGCAGUUUAUGAUGGUCAUGCUGGAUCCCGAGUGGCAAAUUACUGCUCAACACAUUUAUUAGAACACAUCACUACUAACGAAGACUUUAGGGCAGCUGGAAAAUCAGGAUCUGCUCUUGAGCUUUCAGUGGAAAAUGUUAAGAAUGGUAUCAGAACUGGAUUUUUGAAAAUUGAUGAAUACAUGCGUAACUUUUCAGACCUCAGAAACGGGAUGGACAGGAGUGGUUCAACUGCAGUGGGAGUUAUGAUUUCACCUAAGCAUAUCUACUUUAUCAACUGUGGUGAUUCACGUGCUGUUCUGUAUAGGAAUGGACAAGUCUGCUUUUCUACCCAGGAUCACAAACCUUGCAAUCCAAGGGAAAAGGAGCGAAUCCAAAAUGCAGGAGGCAGCGUGAUGAUACAACGUGUUAAUGGUUCAUUAGCAGUAUCUCGUGCUCUGGGGGACUAUGAUUACAAGUGUGUUGAUGGCAAGGGCCCAACAGAACAACUUGUUUCUCCAGAGCCUGAGGUUUAUGAAAUUUUAAGAGCAGAAGAGGAUGAAUUUAUCAUCUUGGCUUGUGAUGGGAUCUGGGAUGUUAUGAGUAAUGAGGAGCUCUGUGAAUAUGUUAAAUCUAGGCUUGAGGUAUCUGAUGACCUGGAAAAUGUGUGCAAUUGGGUAGUGGACACUUGUUUACACAAGGGAAGUCGAGAUAACAUGAGUAUUGUACUAGUUUGCUUUUCAAAUGCUCCCAAGGUCUCAGAUGAAGCGGUGAAAAAAGAUUCAGAGUUGGAUAAGCACUUGGAAUCACGGGUUGAAGAGAUUAUGGAGAAGUCUGGCGAGGAAGGAAUGCCUGAUCUUGCCCAUGUCAUGCGCAUCUUGUCUGCAGAAAAUAUCCCAAAUUUGCCUCCUGGGGGAGGUCUUGCUGGCAAGCGUAAUGUUAUUGAAGCUGUUUAUAGUAGACUGAAUCCACAUAGAGAAAGUGAUGGGAUGGCAGUCUUGGGCACGUCCAUCUGUAAACCUGCUGAGAGCUCUGGUGACAAGAAAGGCAGUGGCUGGCAGACCUUCCAAGCACUCAGAAGCACGCGGACAAAAAGGUUUUUUUGUAAACCCGAACGAAAAAUAAACCCAGCAUUAUAUAAUUAUAGUAUUUGUACUGCUGUUAACCUUUAAUCUUAUAACCCAUUAGUGGAGACAGAGAAGGACUGUCACUGUGCCCUUCAAAAUCAUAUUUUUUCCUGUCCAUGUGAUAAACACCUGUGGCUUCUUGGCAGCACUUUUGGUUUGAUUCCAGGGACUCUUAUGGUUAAAGGCAGGCUUUAAUCUGGCGUUGUUUUCCUUCUCCUAAAAGCACCAUUUAAAUCGGAAGUUACUGGAUUUCUAAACGGUUAAGACCGUCUUCCGACUGGUUUUUAUCAUUCCCAGAUCUCUUCUGAAAGGAGGUGGUGUGCAUAGUUAAUAUGAAAGGAACUGGCUUGUUCUACGCGAAUACAAAUCUGAAUAACUCUUAUAUAUUAGACCUUUUUUUUUUUUUACUUUAGUGACUUCCAGUAUCUAUAUUUAGAAGUGUAUAAUUACUUGAGAUAUAUAUAUAUAUAUAUACACACACACACACAUAUAUAGUGUGUGUGUGUGUAUCUAUGUGUAUAUAUAUACAUAUACACAUGUAUUUUUAGGGCUUUUGGCUUUUUUAGGGCGGGACACGUGAAUCUGGCAGUUGAGACAGAAUUUUUCCUAUAGCGGUGUAACAGUGUACAAUACUAAACUAAUGAAAUGUCUUUCACUAUCAACAAUUUACGUAUCCAUGCUGAUUGCUUUAACACUAGAAAAAAUAUGCCAAAAUAAACUACAUUUUCUAGGCGCUUUCACACCAAAAACACACACACACAGCUGCUUGCCCAUUUGAGAACAGCCAAUAAAGCAAACUCUUUGAAUGAUUUGUGGUUUUGUGUCCCCAGAAGUUUUAACAGUAGUUCUGAAGAUUUGUCAUUUGUGUGUGCUUCAAAGAUAGAGUAAUACAUUUUAUAGCUGGGCAGAUCUCUAACUAUAUAGUUAUAAAAUCUCAAAGCUGAGAAAACCCUGAAUGCCAGAUGAUCUUUCAGCAGCCUCUAGUGUGAGUGUCAGGAAUGAGUUCAUUUCCAUCUUUGAUCAGCUCUGCCUGUCGUGUUGCAUCUCUGCUUCUUCUCCUCAGUUGUCUUAUUAACCCUCGGGGCUAUGAAAAUAAGUAUUUAAAAGCUCCUGGAACCCACAAAAAACACUAAGCCUUGAGAGAGAUGUAGUUGAUCUGAGUCACAUAUGCUAACAACUUUUUAUUUCCCUGAUUAUUCUUCCUGUUCUGUACAAUGACUAGAGAGAAUAAAACUACAUCAGGUACAAAAACCACCUGCCUUCUUAAUUAAUGACCUUUGUUAUAGAUUAACUUCUCCUUUGUUGUCCUGCUUCACUUAGAUCAGAUGACAGAAAACCCAUGACUACACCCUCUGUAAAAGGUGUUCAGUGUACCUUUCCCAAGAGAAACACUGCCUGUAACCAAAUUGCUGUAACUAUGUGCCAACCUUGUAUGAAAAAUGUUGCAAUCCUGCCAAAAACUCCUGUCUCUGCCUAUGGAAAUGAAACCUUGAGCUUCCUUCCUUCAGCACGCUGACUCCAUUCCUUUGGAGCUGGUGCUCCUGGGUGGGCUGUCCUCAAACUCUGCGCUUGAAUUAUCUGUUUAAAUUAGAUUCUGACCUUUUUGAUUAUUUUAGGUUGAUAGGGCCAAAAUUUAACCCCACCUAUUAGGAUGACUUCCAGCAUAUUCUCUUUUCUGUCCCCCAUUAUUUCAUUGAUUACCAUUAUAUAUCCUAACGCCAACUGUAUUCACCAUCCAGGACCCUUUUCUCCCAAUGUGCUCUCAUUUUCUUGAUCAUUCUUAAAGUAUGCAACCCAGAACUGAACAUUUAUGGGUAGCAGAACUGUCUCCUCCUUUAUUCUCAUUAAUACUUUUCUGUUCUUCUAUUUAACACCGAAAUAUUGAACUAGAUUUUCUGGCAACUGCAUGAUACUGUUUGAGUCCUUCGAGCUUAUUUUUGGUUGGUGUUUUGGUUAACCUAUUUUGCAGGACCUUUAUUUGUUCCUAUUAAGUUUUCUUGGGUAAAAUUUAUUAACCUUUUGAGUUGGUUGUGGAUUUAUCUAAGAUAUGUUAGCUAUCUUCUUCUUUCCAGUAACUCCAAAAUUUCAUACAUAAACCUCCCAUACUGAAUGAAACAGGUCCAAGUACUGAGGCCCUGUGGGAGGCCUCAGAAACUUCUCUUCAGUAGGAUGCAAAUUGACCAAUCUUUUACUCAACACCCAUUAGGUAAGAAUUUCAGCAAUGUACUGAUCCACUUAUCUGCUCAUAUUUCUCCAGUUUAUCUACAAGGAUAUCAUAGGAUUUUACAUUCUUUGCAGAAGUCACUUGCAUAUAACCCAGCUUAAGCGGAGGCUUCACUUUGACCUAUUCCUCUAGGUCCUUGCAAAUUUUUGGUGUUGGUUUUUGCUUGUGGUAUUGCUUGCAUCAUUUAUGCAUUUUAAAAAUCCUGAGCUUGUUACAAUUCUUCCUGUGUAACUGCUGAUUUCUUGGUUUUGUUUUUAUUGUUGUUUUAUUAUUUUUAGGUACCUCUGCCUUUUUAUUCUGUAUGUAUGUUAUACUUCAAUUAAAAUAUUUUUAAAAAUA